ACUUCCUCCUCGGGGGCCUCAGAAAACCACAGGGCGCGGGGCCAGGGCGGCGGCCCCCAGGGAGUUGGCAGGAUGGCAGAGGGCAAGGCAGGCGGCGCGGCCGGCCUCUUCGCCAAGCAGGUGCAGAAGAAGUUUAGCAGGGCCCAGGAGAAGGUGCUGCAGAAAUUGGGGAAAGCUGUAGAAACCAAAGAUGAACGAUUUGAACAAAGCGCUAGCAACUUCUACCAACAACAGGCAGAAGGCCACAAGCUGUACAAGGACCUGAAGAACUUCCUUAGUGCAGUCAAAGUGAUGCAUGAAAGUUCAAAAAGAGUGUCAGAAACCCUGCAGGAGAUCUACAGCAGCGAGUGGGACGGUCAUGAGGAGCUGAAGGCCAUCGUAUGGGUAAGAGUGGCUUGAGUUUUACAACUUAUUGGCACUUACUCCUGUUUGCAUCUCAACCUCAGCUUAGCUUCUCUAUCCAAGAAAAUAGGAAAACAAAGGAGCCAGUUCACACUGUGCAUUUGUGUAGCCUCAGUCACUGGGUGGUAGGAAGAAGCUACAACUGUUAAGGUAAAAACAAGUUUUCCCUAAUCUGUGGAUCCCUCUAAUUUUGACCCUCUUCUCCUCUUUAAAACAUUAUGGGAAGUUUUACCUCCUAAAGAUUGGUUGUUUUUUAAAACAAACUUCAUGCAGUUAUACACUCUUAAACUUUCCCAUCUAAGCUCUGGAGUCCAAGGCUUUGACCUUGUGCCCUGUUCUUAAUCUCUGAAUGUAUGUUCAGACUCCCAUAGAGCAGUUCCUUGGGGUAGGGGCUGUCUCUUUUCUUCCUCUGACUAGUCCCCAGAAUCCAACAUGGUAUUCUAAAUACGGUGCUACAAAAAAGGUUUUUGCAGGGAGAAUUUGGGUAUUUCCCUGGUAGGCAGUUGUUGUUGGGAAGUGGAGCCUUCACCAGCCUCUGACUCUAUCCUACAGAAUAAUGAUCUCCUUUGGGAAGACUACGAGGAGAAACUGGCUGACCAGGCUGUAAGGACCAUGGAAAUCUAUGUUGCCCAGUUCAGUGAAAUUAAGGAGAGAAUUGCCAAGCGGGGUCGGAAACUCGUGGACUAUGACAGUGCCCGACACCACCUGGAGGCAGUGCAGAAUGCCAAGAAGAAAGAUGAGGCCAAGACUGCCAAGGCAGAGGAAGAGUUCAACAAAGCCCAGACUGUGUUUGAAGAUCUGAACCAAGAACUACUAGAGGAGCUGCCUAUUCUUUAUAAUAGUCGUAUUGGCUGCUAUGUGACCAUCUUCCAAAACAUUUCCAACUUGAGGGAUGUCUUCUACAGGGAAAUGAGCAAGCUGAACCACAAUCUCUACGAGGUGAUGAGCAAACUGGAGAAGCAACAUUCCAAUAAAGUCUUUGUGGUGAAGGGACUGUCAAGCAGCAGCAGGCGCUCUUUAGUCAUUUCUCCCCCAGUUCGAACAGCUACAGUCUCCAGUCCUCUUACCUCACCUACUAGUCCCUCUACACUUUCCUUGAAGAGUGAGAGUGAAUCUGUCUCAGCAACUGAAGAUCUGGCACCUGAUGCAGCCCAAGGGGAAGACAAUUCUGAGAUCAAGGAGCUCUUAGAAGAGGAGGAAAUAGAGAAGGAAGGAUCUGAAGCAAGCUCCUCUGAGGAAGAUGAGCCUCUACCAGCCUGCAAUGGCCCCGCCCAGGCCCAGCCCUCUCCUACCACUGAAAGGGCCAAGUCCCAGGAGGAAGUUCUCCCCAGCUCCACAACUCCAUCACCAGGCGGAGCCCUGAGCCCUUCAGGGCAGCCUUCAUCAUCUGCCACAGAAGUAGUCCUCCGAACCCGCACCGCAAGUGAAGGAUCUGAACAACCAAAGAAGAGAGCCUCUAUCCAGAGGACCUCAGCACCCCCUAGUAGGCCUCCUCCACCCAGAGCCACUGCAAGCCCCAGGCCCUCCUCAGGGAACAUACCUUCCAGCCCUACAGCCUCUGGAGGGGGUUCACCCACCAGCCCUAGGGCCUCCUUGGGGACUGGGACUGCAAGUCCUAGGACCUCCCUAGAGGUCUCUCCUAAUCCAGAACCACCAGAGAAGCCAGUAAGAACUCCUGAGGCCAAAGAAAAUGAAAACAUCCACAAUCAGAACCCUGAAGAACUUUGUACUUCCCCCACCUUAAUGACAUCUCAGGUUGCUUCAGAGCCUGGAGAGGCAAAGAAGAUGGAAGACAAGGAAAAGGAUAAUAAGCUUAUCUCAGCUAACUCCUCGGAGGGCCAAGACCAGCUUCAAGUCUCCAUGGUACCAGAAAACAACAACCUCACAGCACCUGAACCUCAAGAAGAGGUAUCCACAAGUGAAAAUCCACAACUCUGAAGAGAAACUACCAAGACUCCUCCUGCCCCAAACCUCGCCAGAGAAGCUCUUCAACCAGAGGGUAUAGGUCAGAGGGAUAUAAGAGCCAGCAUCCAUCCCUGGGUUCUCAGUAGGAAUGCUGGUGCUGUCUAAAGACCUGGCAUUAAUGGAGGCGGAGGAGCAGCCUUACGGGAGGGAUGGAGGGAGGCAGGCUGGGGAGAAGAGAACAUUAGACUCAGGGAAUAUUUAAUUCUGGUUUUAGCAUUAUUAGAAUAAGACUUUAUACAUUAACUAAAGUGGAGCUUUAAUCACUAUAAAAAGCAAAAGUAUCUAUAGACACAGACACUUGCCUAUACAGAGACAUAACCACACACACUCAGAGGAUAGUGAACAAAUCUGUCUUUGACUUACGACCCAUUUUGCAAGACUUAAAGCCGGAAGAACACAUUUUCAGAUUGUUAAAUAAAGUCUGAUUCUGACUA